GACUCUGUGCAGAGAGGCUUUGAGGGAUGGUGGAGUCCGGCUCUGCUGGCCUAGAAGCAGAGUGCACCCUCGUGCUCAGUGCUCAGUGGGUGUCUGAACUGAGGGGCAGUUGUCAAUUUGUCUGAGUGGGAAACAUCCUGGAUUUUGUUACUUGGCAAACAGCUGGUGUAAACCUACAGCCAGCAGCAGUCUGGAGCCUGGGAGCCUCCUGAAGUCCCGGGUGAAGCCUCUGGUUUUACCAAUUGCAGGUCGGCUUGGCUGGGAGAGAUGGAUGGCGGGAAAGGGGCAGCAGUCUUGAGGAGCAGGGAGAGGAGUCUUUCCUCCUGCCAGCUUCCCCCGUCAGCCCCAACCCCAGCCCACACAUUGUACCAUCUCUUCUGCUGUGACUGGGUUGCCUGAAUUUGUGGGAGACCCGUGAUCCCAUCCCAGAGUGUGCGGGGGACGGAGGUCUAGUGGGACAAUGUCAUAUUAUAAAUUUGGAAUGCUGAAUAGAAAAUUAUAGAUUUUGAUAUUGAAGGAAAUGAAGCGAAGCCUAAAUGAAAAUUCAGCUCGAAGUACAGCAGGCUGUUUGCCUGUUCCGUUGUUCAAUCAGAAAAAGAGGAACAGACAGCCAUUAACUUCUAAUCCACUUAAAGAUGAUUCAGGUAUCAGUACCCCUUCUGACAAUUAUGAUUUUCCUCCUCUACCUACAGAUUGGGCCUGGGAAGCUGUGAAUCCAGAGUUGGCUCCUGUAAUGAAAACAGUGGACACCGGGCAAAUACCACAUUCAGUUUCUCGUCCUCUGAGAAGUCAAGAUUCUGUCUUUAACUCUAUUCAAUCAAAUACUGGAAGAAGCCAGGGUGGUUGGAGCUACAGAGAUGGUAACAAAAAUACCAGCUUGAAAACUUGGAAUAAAAAUGAUUUUAAGCCUCAAUGUAAACGAACAAACUUAGUGGCAAAUGAUGGAAAAAAUUCUUGUCCAGUGAGUUCGGGAGCUCAACAACAAAAACAAUUAAGAAUACCUGAACCUCCUAACUUAUCUCGCAACAAAGAAACCGAGCUACUCAGACAAACACAUUCAUCAAAAAUAUCUGGCUGCACAAUGAGAGGGCUAGACAAAAACAGUGCACUACAGACACUUAAGCCCAAUUUUCAACAAAAUCAAUAUAAGAAACAAAUGUUGGAUGAUAUUCCAGAAGACAACACCCUGAAGGAAACCUCAUUGUAUCAGUUACAGUUUAAGGAAAAAGCUAGUUCUUUAAGAAUUAUUUCUGCAGUUAUUGAAAGCAUGAAGUAUUGGCGUGAACAUGCACAGAAAACUGUACUUCUUUUUGAAGUAUUAGCUGUUCUUGAUUCAGCUGUUACACCUGGCCCAUAUUAUUCGAAGACUUUUCUUAUGAGGGAUGGGAAAAAUACUCUGCCUUGUGUCUUUUAUGAAAUCGAUCGUGAACUUCCGAGACUGAUUAGAGGCCGAGUUCAUAGAUGUGUUGGCAACUAUGACCAGAAAAAGAACAUUUUCCAAUGUGUUUCUGUCAGACCGGCGUCUGUUUCUGAACAAAAAACUUUCCAGGCAUUUGUCAAAAUUGCAGAUGUUGAGAUGCAGUAUUAUAUUAAUGUGAUGAAUGAAACUUAAGUAGUGAUAAAAGGAAGUUUAGCAUAAAUUAUAGCAGUUUUCUGUUAUUGCUUAAUUUACCAUCUCCAUAGUUUUAUAGCUACUAUUGUAUUUCACUUGUUGAAUUAAAGUAUUUGAAUUCUUUUAAA